UUUUCCUACUGCAGCCAUGGGUGCCCUAUGGAGCUGGUGGAUACUCUGGGCUGGAGCAACCCUCCUGUGGGGAUUGACCCAGGAGGCUUCAGUGGACCUCAAGAACACUGGCAGAGAGGAAUUCCUCACAGCCUUCCUGCAGAACUAUCAGCUGGCCUACAGCAAGGCCUACCCCCGCCUCCUUAUCUCCAGUCUGUCAGAGAGCCCCGCUUCAGUCUCCAUCCUCAGCCAGGCAGACAACACCUCAAAGAAGGUCACAGUGAGGCCCGGGGAGUCGGUCAUGGUCAACAUCAGUGCCAAGGCUGAGAUGAUAGGCAGCAAGAUCUUCCAGCAUGCGGUGGUGAUCCAUUCUGACUAUGCCAUCUCUGUGCAGGCACUAAAUGCCAAGCCUGACACAGCGGAGCUGACACUGCUGCGGCCCAUCCAGGCCCUAGGCACCGAGUAUUUUGUGCUCACACCCCCCGGCACCUCAGCCAGGAAUGUCAAGGAGUUUGCCGUGGUGGCCGGUGCCGCAGGUGCCUCGGUCAGUGUCACGCUGAAGGGGUCAGUGACAUUCAAUGGCAAGUUCUAUCCAGCAGGCGAUGUCCUAAGAGUGACUCUACAGCCCUACAAUGUGGCCCAGCUACAGAGCUCAGUGGAUCUCUCGGGGUCAAAGGUCACAGCUAGUAGCCCCGUGGCUGUCCUCUCUGGCCACAGCUGUGCGCAGAAACAUACGACCUGCAACCAUGUGGUUGAGCAGCUGCUACCCACGUCUGCCUGGGGCACCCACUAUGUAGUACCCACGCUGGCCUCCCAAUCUCGCUAUGAUUUGGCCUUCGUUGUGGCCAGCCAGGCCACAAAGCUGACCUACAACCAUGGGGGUAUCACUGGCUCCCGUGGGCUCCAGGCAGGUGAUGUGGUAGAGUUUGAGGUCCGGCCAUCCUGGCCACUCUACCUGUCUGCAAAUGUGGGCAUCCAGGUCCUGUUGUUUGGCACAGGUGCCAUAAGGAAUGAAGUGACUUAUGACCCCUACCUGGUCCUGAUCCCAGAUGUGGCGGCCUACUGCCCAGCCUAUGUGGUCAAGAGUGUACCAGGCUGUGAGGGCGUGGCCCUGGUAGUGGCACAGACGAAGGCUAUCAGCGGGCUGACCAUAGAUGGGCAUGCAGUGGGGGCCAAGCUCACCUGGGAGGCUGUGCCAGGCAGUGAGUUCUCGUAUGCUGAAGUGGAGCUCGGCACAGCUGACAUGAUCCACACGGCCGAGGCCACCACCAACUUGGGACUGCUCACCUUCGGGCUGGCCAAGGCUAUAGGCUACGCAACAGCUGCUGAUUGCGGCCGGACUGUACUGUCCCCAGUGGAGCCCUCCUGCGAAGGCAUGCAGUGCGCAGCCGGGCAGCGCUGCCAGGUGGUAGGCGGGAAGGCCGGGUGUGUGGCGGAGUCCACCGCUGUCUGCCGCGCCCAGGGCGACCCCCAUUACACCACCUUCGACGGCCGUCGCUACGACAUGAUGGGCACCUGUUCGUACACGAUGGUGGAGCUGUGCAGCGAGGACGACACCCUGCCCGCCUUCAGCGUGGAGGCCAAGAACGAGCACCGGGGCAGCCGCCGCGUCUCCUACGUGGGCCUCGUCACUGUGCGCGCCUACAGCCACUCUGUGUCGCUGACCCGCGGUGAAGUUGGCUUCGUCCUGGUUGACAACCAGCGCUCGCGCCUGCCAGUCUCCCUGAGUGAGGGUCGCCUGCGUGUGUACCAGAGCGGACCACGGGCCGUGGUGGAGCUGGUCUUUGGGCUGGUGGUCACUUAUGACUGGGACUGCCAGCUGGCACUCAGCCUGCCUGCACGCUUCCAAGACCAGGUGUGCGGGCUGUGUGGCAACUAUAAUGGUGACCCAGCAGACGACUUCCUCACGCCUGACGGGGCUCUGGCUCCUGACGCUGUGGAGUUCGCAAGUAGCUGGAAGCUGGAUGAUGGGGACUACCUGUGUGAGGAUGGCUGCCAGAACAACUGUCCCGCCUGCACCCCAGGCCAGGCCCAACACUAUGAGGGCGACCGACUCUGUGGCAUGCUGACCAAGCUCGAUGGCCCCUUCGCUGUCUGCCAUGACACCCUGGACCCCAGGCCCUUCCUGGAGCAGUGUGUAUAUGACCUGUGUGUGGUCGGUGGGGAGCGGCUCAGCCUGUGCCGUGGCCUCAGCGCCUAUGCCCAGGCCUGUCUGGAGCUUGGCAUCUCGGUUGGGGACUGGAGAUCACCAGCCAACUGCCCCCUGUCCUGCCCUGCCAACAGCCGCUAUGAGCUCUGCGGCCCUGCUUGCCCGACCUCCUGCAACGGGGCUGCGGCGCCGUCCAACUGCUCCGGGCGCCCCUGCGUGGAGGGCUGCGUGUGCCUCCCAGGCUUCGUGGCCAGCGGCGGCGCCUGCGUGCCGGCCUCGUCGUGUGGCUGCACCUUCCAGGGUCUCCAGCUCGCUCCGGGCCAGGAAGUGUGGGCGGACGAGUUGUGCCAAAGGCGCUGCACCUGCAACGGCGCCACCCAUCAGGUCACCUGCCGCGACAAGCAGAGCUGCCCGGCGGGUGAGCGCUGCAGCGUCCAGAACGGCCUCCUGGGCUGCUACCCCGAUCGCUUCGGGACCUGCCAGGGGUCCGGGGACCCACACUAUGUGAGCUUCGACGGCCGGCGCUUCGACUUCAUGGGCACCUGCACGUACCUGCUGGUCGGCUCAUGCGGCCAGAACGCAGCGCUGCCUGCCUUCCGGGUGCUGGUGGAAAACGAGCAUCGGGGCAGCCAGACUGUGAGCUACACGCGCGCCGUGCGGGUGGAGGCCCGCGGGGUGAAGGUGGCCGUGCGCCGGGAGUACCCCGGGCAAGUGCUGGUGGAUGACGUCCUUCAGUAUCUGCCCUUCCAAGCAGCAGAUGGGCAGGUGCAGGUGUUCCGACAGGGCAGGGAUGCCGUCGUGCGCACGGACUUUGGCCUGACUGUCACUUAUGACUGGAAUGCACGAGUGACUGCCAAGGUGCCCAGCAGCUAUGCUGAGGCCCUGUGUGGACUCUGUGGGAACUUCAACGGGGACCCAGCUGAUGACCUGGCUCUGCGGGGUGGGGGUCAAGCUGCCAAUGCACUGGCCUUUGGGAACAGCUGGCAAGAAGAGACGAGGCCCGGCUGUGGAGCAACUGAACCGGGUGACUGUCCCAAGCUGGACUCCCUGGUGGCCCAGCAGCUGCAGAGCAAGAAUGAGUGUGGAAUCCUUGCCGACCCCAAGGGGCCCUUCCGGGAGUGCCAUAGCAAGCUGGACCCCCAGGGUGCCGUGCGCGACUGUGUCUAUGACCGCUGCCUGCUGCCAGGCCAGUCUGGGCCACUGUGUGACGCACUGGCCACCUAUGCUGCUGCAUGCCAGGCUGCUGGAGCCACAGUGCACCCCUGGAGGAGUGAAGAACUUUGCCCCAGGCUGGAGGAUCUCUGCCAGCUCUCGGGAGGCCUGGUCUCGCUCCUGUGCCCACCCCACAGCCACUAUGAGGCGUGUUCCUACGGUGCCCGCUGUCCUGUGGAGACCUCCCAGUGCGAGGGCUGUGAGUCGGCCUGCCGUGAAGGCUGUGUCUGCGAUGCUGGCUUCGUGCUCAGUGGUGACACGUGUGUACCUGUGGGCCAGUGUGGCUGCCUCCACGAUGACCGCUACUACCCACUGGGCCAGACCUUCUACCCUGGCCCUGGGUGUGAUUCCCUUUGCCGCUGCCGGGAGGGCGGUGAGGUGUCCUGUGAGCCCUCCAGCUGCGGCCCGCAUGAGACCUGCCGGCCAUCCGGUGGCAGCUUGGGCUGCGUGGCCGUGGGCUCUACCACCUGCCAGGCGUCGGGAGAUCCCCACUACACCACCUUCGAUGGCCACCGCUUCGACUUCAUGGGCACCUGCGUGUAUGUGCUGGCUCAGACCUGCGGCACCCGGCCUGGCCUGCAUCGGUUUGCCGUCCUGCAGGAGAACGUGGCCUGGGGUAAUGGGCGAGUCAGUGUGACCAGGGUGAUCACGGUCCAGGUGGCAAACUUCACCCUGCGGCUGGAGCAGAGACAGUGGAAGGUCACGGUGAACGGUGUGGACAUGAAGCUGCCCGUGGUGCUGGCCAACGGCCAGAUCCGUGCCUCCCAGCAUGGUUCAGAUGUUGUGAUUGAGACCGACUUCGGCCUGCGUGUGGCCUACGACCUUGUGUACUAUGUGCGGGUCACCGUCCCUGGAAACUACUACCAGCUGAUGUGUGGCCUGUGUGGGAACUACAAUGGCGACCCCAAGGAUGACUUCCAGAAGCCCAAUGGCUCGCAGGCAGGCAACGCCAAUGAGUUCGGCAACUCCUGGGAGGAGGUGGUGUCCGACUCUCCCUGCCUGCCGCCGCCCACCUGCCCGCCGGGGAGCGAGGGCUGUAUCCCCAGCGAGGAGUGUCCUCCCGAGCUGGAGAAGAAGUAUCAGAAGGAGGAGUUCUGUGGGCUCCUCUCCAGCCCCACAGGGCCACUGUCCUCCUGCCACAAGCUGGUGGAUCCCCAGGGUCCCUUGAAAGAUUGCAUCUUUGAUCUCUGCCUGGGUGGUGGGAACCUGAGCAUUCUCUGCAGCAACAUCCAUGCCUACGUGAGUGCUUGCCAGGUGGCUGGAGGCCACGUGGAGCCCUGGAGGAAUGAAACUUUCUGUCCCAUGGAAUGCCCUCAGAACAGUCACUACGAGCUCUGUGCGGACACCUGCUCCCUGGGCUGCUCGGCUCUCAGUGCCCCUCUGCAGUGCCCAGAUGGGUGUGCUGAGGGCUGCCAGUGUGACUCCGGCUUCCUCUACAACGGCCAAGCCUGCGUGCCCAUCCAGCAAUGUGGCUGCUACCACAAUGGUGCCUACUAUGAGCCGGAGCAGACAGUCCUCAUUGACAACUGUCGGCAGCAGUGCACGUGCCAUGCGGGUAAAGUCGUGGUGUGCCAGGAACACAGCUGCAAGCCGGGGCAGGUGUGCCAGCCCUCCGGAGGCAUCCUGAGCUGCGUCACCAAAGACCCGUGCCACGGCGUGACAUGCCGGCCACAGGAGACAUGCAAGGAGCAGGGUGGCCAGGGCGUGUGCCUGCCCAACUAUGAGGCCACGUGCUGGCUGUGGGGCGACCCACACUACCACUCCUUCGAUGGCCGGAAGUUUGACUUCCAGGGCACCUGUAACUAUGUGCUGGCAACAACUGGCUGCCCGGGGGUCAGCACCCAGGGCCUGACACCCUUCACCGUCACCACCAAGAACCAGAACCGGGGCAACCCUGCUGUGUCCUACGUGAGAGUCGUCACCGUGGCUGCCCUCGGCACCAACAUCUCCAUCCACAAGGACGAGAUCGGCAAAGUCCGGGUGAACGGUGUGCUCACAGCCUUGCCUGUCUCUGUGGCCGACGGGCGGAUUUCAGUGACCCAGGGUGCAUCGAAGGCACUGCUGGUGGCUGACUUUGGACUGCAAGUCAGCUAUGACUGGAACUGGCGGGUAGACGUGACGCUGCCCAGCAGCUAUCAUGGCGCAGUGUGCGGGCUCUGCGGUAACAUGGACCGCAACCCCAACAAUGACCAGGUCUUCCCUAAUGGCACACUGGCUCCCUCCAUACCCAUCUGGGGCGGCAGCUGGCGAGCCCCAGGCUGGGACCCACUGUGUUGGGACGAAUGUCGGGGGUCCUGCCCAACGUGCCCUGAGGACCGGUUGGAGCAGUACGAGGGCCCUGGCUUCUGCGGACCCCUGGCCCCCGGCACAGGGGGCCCUUUCACCACCUGCCAUGCUCAUGUGCCACCUGAGAGCUUCUUCAAGGGCUGUGUUCUGGACGUCUGCAUGGGUGGUGGGGACCGUGACAUUCUUUGCAAGGCUCUGGCUUCCUAUGUGGCCGCCUGCCAGGCUGCUGGGGUUGUCAUCGAAGACUGGCGGGCACAGGUUGGCUGUGAGAUCACCUGCCCAGAAAACAGCCACUAUGAGGUCUGUGGCCCACCCUGCCCGGCCAGCUGUCCGUCCCCUGCACCCCUUACGACGCCAGCCGUAUGUGAGGGCCCCUGUGUGGAGGGCUGCCAGUGCGACGCGGGUUUCGUGUUAAGUGCUGACCGCUGUGUUCCCCUCAACAACGGCUGCGGCUGCUGGGCCAAUGGCACCUACCACGAGGCGGGCAGUGAGUUUUGGGCUGAUGGCACCUGCUCCCAGUGGUGUCGCUGCGGGCCUGGGGGUGGCUCGCUGGUCUGCACACCUGCCAGCUGUGGGCUGGGUGAAGUGUGUGGCCUCCUGCCAUCCGGCCAGCACGGCUGCCAGCCCGUCAGCACAGCUGAGUGCCAGGCGUGGGGUGACCCCCAUUACGUCACUCUGGAUGGGCACCGAUUCGAUUUCCAAGGCACCUGCGAGUACCUGCUGAGUGCACCCUGCCACGGACCACCCUUGGGGGCUGAGAACUUCACUGUCACUGUAGCCAAUGAGCACCGGGGCAGCCAGGCUGUCAGCUACACCCGCAGUGUCACCCUGCAAAUCUACAACCACAGCCUGACACUGAGUGCCCGCUGGCCCCGGAAGCUACAGGUGGACGGCGUGUUCGUCACUCUGCCCUUCCAGCUGGACUCGCUCCUGCACGCACACCUGAGCGGCGCCGACGUGGUGGUGACCACAACCUCAGGGCUCUCGCUGGCUUUCGAUGGGGACAGCUUCGUGCGCCUGCGCGUGCCGGCGGCGUACGCGGGCUCUCUCUGUGGCUUAUGCGGGAACUACAACCAGGACCCCGCAGACGACCUGAAGGCGGUGGGCGGGAAGCCCGCCGGAUGGCAGGUGGGCGGCGCCCAGGGCUGCGGGGAAUGUGUGUCCAAGCCAUGCCCGUCGCCGUGCACCCCAGAGCAGCAAGAGUCCUUCGGCGGCCCGGACGCCUGCGGCGUGAUCUCCGCCACCGACGGCCCGCUGGCGCCCUGCCACGGCCUUGUGCCGCCCGCGCAGUACUUCCAGGGCUGCUUGCUGGACGCCUGCCAAGUUCAGGGCCAUCCUGGAGGCCUCUGUCCUGCAGUGGCCACCUACGUGGCAGCCUGUCAGGCCGCUGGGGCCCAGCUCCGCGAGUGGAGGCGGCCGGACUUCUGUCCCUUCCAGUGCCCUGCCCACAGCCACUACGAGCUCUGCGGUGACUCCUGUCCUGGGAGCUGCCCGAGCCUGUCGGCACCCGAGGGCUGUGAGUCGGCCUGCCGUGAAGGCUGUGUCUGCGAUGCUGGCUUCGUGCUCAGUGGUGACACGUGUGUACCUGUGGGCCAGUGUGGCUGCCUCCACGAUGACCGCUACUACCCACUGGGCCAGACCUUCUACCCUGGCCCUGGGUGUGAUUCCCUUUGCCGCUGCCGGGAGGGCGGUGAGGUGUCCUGUGAGCCCUCCAGCUGCGGCCCGCAUGAGACCUGCCGGCCAUCCGGUGGCAGCUUGGGCUGCGUGGCCGUGGGCUCUACCACCUGCCAGGCGUCGGGAGAUCCCCACUACACCACCUUCGAUGGCCACCGCUUCGACUUCAUGGGCACCUGCGUGUAUGUGCUGGCUCAGACCUGCGGCACCCGGCCUGGCCUGCAUCGGUUUGCCGUCCUGCAGGAGAACGUGGCCUGGGGUAAUGGGCGAGUCAGUGUGACCAGGGUGAUCACGGUCCAGGUGGCAAACUUCACCCUGCGGCUGGAGCAGAGACAGUGGAAGGUCACGGUGAACGGUGUGGACAUGAAGCUGCCCGUGGUGCUGGCCAACGGCCAGAUCCGUGCCUCCCAGCAUGGUUCAGAUGUUGUGAUUGAGACCGACUUCGGCCUGCGUGUGGCCUACGACCUUGUGUACUAUGUGCGGGUCACCGUCCCUGGAAACUACUACCAGCUGAUGUGUGGCCUGUGUGGGAACUACAACGGCGACCCCAAGGAUGACUUCCAGAAGCCCAAUGGCUCGCAGGCAGGCAACGCCAAUGAGUUCGGCAACUCCUGGGAGGAGGUGGUGCCCGACUCUCCCUGCCUGCCGCCGCCCACCUGCCCGCCGGGGAGCGCGGGCUGUAUCCCCAGCGACAAGUGUCCUCCCGAGCUGGAGAAGAAGUAUCAGAAGGAGGAGUUCUGUGGGCUCCUCUCCAGCCCCACAGGGCCACUGUCCUCCUGCCACAAGCUGGUGGAUCCCCAGGGUCCCUUGAAAGAUUGCAUCUUUGAUCUCUGCCUGGGUGGUGGGAACCUGAGCAUUCUCUGCAGCAACAUCCAUGCCUACGUGAGUGCUUGCCAGGCGGCUGGAGGCCACGUGGAGCCCUGGAGGAAUGAAACUUUCUGUCCCAUGGAAUGCCCUCAGAACAGUCACUACGAGCUCUGUGCGGACACCUGCUCCCUGGGCUGCUCGGCUCUCAGUGCCCCUCUGCAGUGCCCAGAUGGGUGUGCUGAGGGCUGCCAGUGUGACUCCGGCUUCCUCUACAACGGCCAAGCCUGCGUGCCCAUCCAGCAAUGUGGCUGCUACCACAAUGGUGUCUACUAUGAGCCGGAGCAGACAGUCCUCAUUGACAACUGUCGGCAGCAGUGCACGUGCCAUGUGGGUAAAGUCGUGGUGUGCCAGGAACACAGCUGCAAGCCGGGGCAGGUGUGCCAGCCCUCCGGAGGCAUCCUGAGCUGCGUCACCAAAGACCCGUGCCACGGCGUGACAUGCCGGCCACAGGAGACAUGCAAGGAGCAGGGUGGCCAGGGCGUGUGCCUGCCCAACUAUGAGGCCACGUGCUGGCUGUGGGGCGACCCACACUACCACUCCUUCGAUGGCCGGAAGUUUGACUUCCAGGGCACCUGUAACUAUGUGCUGGCAACAACUGGCUGCCCGGGGGUCAGCACCCAGGGCCUGACACCCUUCACCGUCACCACCAAGAACCAGAACCGGGGCAACCCUGCUGUGUCCUACGUGAGAGUCGUCACCGUGGCUGCCCUCGGCACCAACAUCUCCAUCCACAAGGACGAGAUCGGCAAAGUCCGGGUGAACGGUGUGCUCACAGCCUUGCCUGUCUCCGUGGCCGACGGGCGGAUUUCAGUGGCCCAGGGUGCAUCGAAGGCACUGCUGGUGGCUGACUUUGGACUGCAAGUCAGCUAUGACUGGAACUGGCGGGUAGACGUGACGCUCCCCAGCAGCUAUCAUGGCGCAGUGUGCGGGCUCUGCGGUAACAUGGACCGCAACCCCAACAAUGACCAGGUCUUCCCUAAUGGCACACUGGCUCCCUCCAUACCCAUCUGGGGCGGCAGCUGGCGAGCCCCAGGCUGGGACCCACUGUGUUGGGACGAAUGUCGGGGGUCCUGCCCAACGUGCCCUGAGGACCGGUUGGAGCAGUACGAGGGCCCUGGCUUCUGCGGACCCCUUUCAUCUGGCACAGGGGGCCCCUUCACCACCUGCCAUGCUCAUGUGCCACCUGAGAGCUUCUUCAAGGGCUGUGUUCUGGACGUCUGCAUGGGUGGUGGGGACCGUGACAUUCUUUGCAAGGCUCUGGCUUCCUACGUGGCCGCCUGCCAGGCCGCUGGGGUUGUCAUCGAAGACUGGCGGGCACAGGUUGGCUGUGAGAUCACCUGCCCAGAAAACAGCCACUAUGAGGUCUGUGGCCCACCCUGCCCAGCCAGCUGUCCGUCCCCUGCACCCCUUACGACGCCAGCCGUAUGUGAGGGCCCCUGUGUGGAGGGCUGCCAGUGCGACGCGGGUUUCGUGUUAAGUGCUGACCGCUGUGUUCCCCUCAACAACGGCUGCGGCUGCUGGGCCAAUGGCACCUACCACGAGGCGGGCAGUGAGUUUUGGGCUGAUGGCACCUGCUCCCAGUGGUGUCGCUGCGGGCCUGGGGGUGGCUCGCUGGUCUGCACACCUGCCAGCUGUGGGCUGGGUGAAGUGUGUGGCCUCCUGCCAUCCGGCCAGCACGGCUGCCAGCCCGUCAGCACAGCUGAGUGCCAGGCGUGGGGUGACCCCCAUUACGUCACUCUGGAUGGGCACCGAUUCGAUUUCCAAGGCACCUGCGAGUACCUGCUGAGUGCACCCUGCCACGGACCACCCUUGGGGGCUGAGAACUUCACUGUCACUGUAGCCAAUGAGCACCGGGGCAGCCAGGCUGUCAGCUACACCCGCAGUGUCACCCUGCAAAUCUACAACCACAGCCUGACACUGAGUGCCCGCUGGCCCCGGAAGCUACAGGUCGACGGCGUGUUCGUGGCUCUGCCUUUCCAGCUGGACUCGCUCCUGCACGCACACCUGAGCGGCGCCGACGUGGUGGUGACCACAACCUCAGGGCUCUCGCUGGCUUUCGAUGGGGACAGCUUCGUGCGCCUGCGCGUGCCGGCGGCGUACGCGGCCUCUCUCUGUGGCUUAUGCGGGAACUACAACCAGGACCCCGCAGACGACCUCAAGGCUGUGGGCGGGAAGCCCGCUGGAUGGCAGGUGGGCGGGGCCCAGGGCUGCGGGGAAUGUGUGUCCAAGCCAUGCCCGUCGCCGUGCACCCCAGAGCAGCAGGAGUCCUUCGGCGGCCCGGACGCCUGCGGCGUGAUCUCCGCCACCGACGGCCCGCUGGCACCCUGCCACGGCCUUGUGCCGCCCGCGCAGUACUUCCAGGGCUGCUUGCUGGACGCCUGCCAAGUUCAGGGCCAUCCUGGAGGCCUCUGUCCUGCAGUGGCUACCUACGUGGCAGCCUGUCAGGCCGCUGGGGCCCAGCUCGGCGAGUGGAGGCGGCCGGACUUCUGUCCCUUGCAGUGCCCUGCCCACAGCCACUAUGAGCUCUGCGGUGACUCCUGCCCUGUGAGCUGCCCGAGCCUCUCAGCACCCGAGGGCUGUGAGUCGGCCUGCCGUGAAGGCUGUGUCUGCGAUGCUGGCUUCGUACUCAGUGGUGACACCUGCGUACCCGUGGGCCAGUGUGGCUGCCUCCAUGAUGGCCGCUACUACCCACUGGGCGAGGUCUUCUACCCGGGCCCUGAGUGUGAGCGGCGCUGUGAGUGUGGGCCAGGUGGCCAUGUCACCUGCCAGGAGGGCGCAGCCUGUGGGCCCCAUGAGGAGUGCCGGUUAGAGGAUGGUGUCCAGGCCUGUCAUGCCACAGGCUGUGGCCGCUGCCUGGCCAACGGGGGCAUCCACUACAUCACCCUUGAUGGCCGUGUCUACGACCUGCAUGGCUCCUGCUCCUAUGUCUUGGCCCAAGUCUGCCACCCAAAGCCUGGGGACGAGGACUUUUCCAUCGUGCUUGAGAAGAAUGCAGCUGGAGAUCUCCAACGCCUCCUGGUUACUGUGGCUGGCCAGGUUGUGAGCCUAGCUCAGGGGCAGCAGGUCACCGUGGACGGCGAGGCUGUGGCCCUGCCUGUGGCUGUGGGCCGCGUGCGGGUGACCGCCGAGGGCCGAAACAUGGUUCUGCAGACGACCAAGGGGCUGCGGCUUCUCUUUGAUGGCGAUGCCCACCUCCUCAUGUCCAUCCCCAGCCCCUUCCGUGGACGGCUCUGUGGCCUCUGUGGGAACUUCAAUGGCAACUGGAGUGACGACUUUGUCCUGCCCAAUGGCUCAGCAGCGUCCAGUGUGGAGACCUUCGGGGCUGCAUGGCGGGCGCCCGGCUCCUCCAAGGGCUGUGGCGAGGGCUGCGGGCCCCAAGGCUGCCCAGUGUGCUUGGCAGAGGAGACUGCACCCUAUGAGAGCAACGAGGCCUGCGGGCAGCUCCGGAACCCCCAGGGCCCCUUCGCGACCUGCCAGGCGGUGCUGAGUCCCUCUGAGUACUUCCGCCAAUGCGUAUACGACCUGUGCGCGCAAAAGGGUGACAAAGCCUUCCUGUGCCGCAGCCUGGCAGCCUACACGGCGGCCUGUCAGGCAGCUGGCGUGGCCGUGAAGCCCUGGAGGACAGACAGCUUCUGCCCGCUCCAUUGCCCCGCCCACAGCCACUACUCCAUCUGCACUCGCACCUGCCAGGGAUCCUGUGCGGCUCUCUCCGGCCUCACGGGCUGCACCACCCGCUGUUUUGAGGGCUGUGAGUGCGACGACCGCUUCCUGCUUUCCCAGGGUGUCUGCAUCCCUGUCCAAGAUUGUGGCUGCACCCAUAAUGGCCGAUACUUGCCGGUAAACUCCUCCCUGCUGACCUCAGACUGCAGCGAGCGCUGUUCCUGUUCCUCAAGCUCUGGCCUGACAUGCCAGGCAGCUGGCUGCCCACCAGGCCGUGUAUGUGAGGUCAAGGCUGAAGCCCGGAACUGCUGGGCCACCCGUGGUCUCUGUGUCCUGUCUGUGGGUGCCAACCUCACCACCUUUGAUGGGGCCCGUGGUGCCACCACCUCUCCUGGUGUCUAUGAGCUCUCUUCCCGCUGCCCAGGACUACAGAAUACCAUCCCCUGGUACCGUGUAGUUGCCGAAGUCCAGAUCUGCCAUGGCAAAACGGAGGCUGUGGGCCAGGUCCACAUCUUCUUCCAGGAUGGGAUGGUGACGUUGACUCCAAACAAGGGUGUGUGGGUGAAUGGUCUCCGAGUGGAUCUCCCAGCUGAGAAGUUAGCAUCUGUGUCCGUGAGUCGUACACCUGAUGGCUCCCUGCUAGUCCGCCAGAAGGCAGGGGUCCAGGUGUGGCUUGGAGCCAAUGGGAAGGUGGCUGUGAUUGUCAGCAAUGACCAUGCUGGGAAACUGUGUGGGGCCUGUGGAAACUUUGACGGGGACCAGACCAAUGAUUGGCAUGACUCCCAGGAGAAGCCAGCGAUGGAGAAAUGGAGAGCGCAGGACUUCUCCCCAUGUUAUGGCUGAUCAGUCAUCCACCAGGAACGAAGAUUUCCUGAAGAAGACCUGGUCCCUCUGGAGGUUGCAGUGGCUGAAGGAUGCAUCAUGUGCUCCUACCCUGCUCUACCGCUUUUCUGGGUCACAGAGGCCAAAUGUGAGAGCAUUGAAUAAAUAUCUUAAGCUAAGCUGCA